AGGCUCGACGCUACCGUGUAUGAGGAACUUUGAUCCUUGCGGGCCACCAUUCCGGAAGUAGAAUUUAGAGGAAGAAAAUACCGGAGUUGCAGGGUAUAGGUAAAUUUCUCAAGGUUAUAGGUUGGGGUUCUUAGAACUUUUUGUGGUGUGUGUUGGCCUAGAGCGACUCAGAAGCGUUAGUGACUUCACCUAAAAAAGCUAACCUCUCUGCUGAGCGCGACCGGUAUGCGGCGCAGGAUGAGCCUCAGGGCUUCUGUUAAGAGUCUGUCUGAGAAAGCCGGUCUGCGCUGUUCCUCGGUGGCGACCUUAAUUAUGAGAUGAGCUAAUGCUUUACUGACUUAACCAUGGCGCAGCGGGCAGUGUGGCUCAUAAGCCACGAACCGGGAACUCCACUUUGUGGCACCGUGAGAUUCUCCAGGGAUUGGCAAGAAGACUCAGGGUACCUGUCAUUCACUAUAAGACGGUAUCCAACUGUUGAAAAACGAGCCAGAGUCUUCAAUGGAGCAAGUUAUGUGCCUGUUCCUGAAGAUGGUCCCUUUCUUAAAGCACUGCUCUUUGAACUUAGAUUAUUGGAUGAUGAUAAAGACUUCGUUGAGAGUCGUGAUAGCUGUUCACGCAUCAAUAAAACAUCCAUUUAUGGACUCCUGAUAGGAGGUGAAGAACUCUGGCCAGUUGUUGCUUUUCUGAAGAAUGACAUGAUAUAUGCUUGUGUUCCACUAGUUGAACAAACUCUGUCCCCUCGUCCGCCACUAAUUAGUGUCAGUGGAGUUUCACAAGGCUUUGAAUUUCUUUUUGGGAUACAGGAUUUUCUUUAUUCAGGUCAAAAAAAUGACUCUGAGCUGAAUACAAAAUUGAGCCAGUUGCCUGACUUGCUUCUGCAGGCUUGUCCAUUUGGUACUUUAUUAGAUGCCAACUUACAGAAUUCAUUAGAUAAUACCAAUUUUGCAUCUGUGACUCAGCCACAGAAACAGCCAGCUUGGAAAACUGGGACGUACAAAGGAAAACCACAAGUUUCUAUUUCUAUCACUGAAAAGGUAAAAUCCAUGCAAUAUGAUAAACAGGGUAUAGCAGAUACAUGGCAAGUUGUUGGAACAGUGACUUGCAAGUGUGAUUUGGAAGGAAUCAUGCCAAAUGUUACCAUCAGCUUGAGUCUCCCCACCAAUGGAUCUCCACUUCAGGAUAUUCUAGUUCACCCUUGUGUAACUUCUCUUGACUCUGCAAUUCUGACUUCUAGUAGUAUUGAUGCAAUGGAUGACUCUGCAUUUAGUGGGCCUUACAAAUUUCCAUUCACUCCACCUUUAGAGUCAUUCAACUUAUGCUUCUACACUUCCCAGGUCCCUGUCCCACCAAUUUUGGGUUUUUAUCAAAUGAAGGAGGAAGAAGUACAACUAAGAAUAACCAUUAAUUUAAAACUUCAUGAAAGUGUGAAAAAUAAUUUUGAAUUCUGUGAAGCCCAUAUACCUUUUUACAAUAGAGGUCCAAUUACACAUUUGGAAUACAAAACUAGUUUUGGCCAGCUUGAAGUAUUUCGAGAGAAAAGCUUAUUGAUCUGGAUUAUUGGCCAGAAGUUCCCAAAAUCAAUGGAAAUUAGUCUUUCUGGAACUGUAACUUUUGGAGCCAAGAGCCAUGAGAAGCAGCCAUUUGACCCAAUUUGUACUGGAGAAACAGCAUAUUUAAAGCUUCAUUUUAGGAUCUUAGAUUACACACUUACUGGAUGUUAUGCAGAUCAGCAUUCAGUUCAAGUUUUUGCAUCAGGAAAACCAAAAAUAAGUGCACACCGGAAACUAAUUUCUUCUGAUUAUUACAUCUGGAAUUCUAAAGCCCCUGCUCCAGUAACAUAUGGAUCAUUAUUAUUGUAAUAGUCUCAUGUUUAAAUGGGAUUAUAUAAUGAUAACAGUUUAAAGAAAAUCAUAAUCUUAUAUUUUUAAUGUGGAUGCAUAUAACCUGUGAGUGAAAAAUCACUGAAUGAUUUAAUUGUAAAAGUAGUCUUAUGUGGUGUUUGUAGUCUGAUAGAGCUUGAAAGGACAUUUUAAAAGCUAAUGUCUCCAAUUUUGUUAACCUUCGAUUUUAUGCCAGUAUAAUUCAGAACAUAGAAAAGUAAUGAUUCACUUGGGCUCAUUUUAGACUGGUCCUGGGUCACCCUGCCACACUUGUUUCCUAGUGUUUCUGUGGCAGACAUUGCUAAUCAAUUACAGCCCUUUUCUGUACUGAGCCUUGGAUAAAGGGUCAGGCUCCUUUUUAGUUCAGAGAUUCAGGCAGCCACUCCCAGUGGGUUGUAGAUAAUGUGCAAGAUAAAAACUAUUUUCUCUUCCAAAUCUAAGUACUAAGCUCCUAGUAUAAGGUGUUGUUACAGAAUACCAGAGACCAUGUUAGAGACAACUACAUCUCUUCAAAAAACAGCCAACAGAGACAAAGGAAAAGUGUUUAAAUAGUAAGCUGUUCUUCUUAAUCAGAACUAUCCUAUUGACUAAUAAAUAAUCUGCAUAAUUCUACUUAAGGUGUGUAAUCUCUGUUCUAGAGUUAGUUUUUAAGUAAGCUUGUUAAUCUGCCACUUUGACAUUUUGCUUAGGAUGUCAGUAGCCAUAUUAAGAUGUGUAGAAUACCUUCAGAAGAUGAUCAUAGUGUUUUGUAAUCAUUUAAUGUCUGCAGCCAAAUUUUUAAAGGUAAUUUAGACCUAAUACUGCUCUUGCUGUGUCUUAUUAAGUUAAAAUUAAUGAAUGAAUUCUGGUAAAAAUUCAAAAGGCACUCUGUGAGUAGAGAGUAUCAUUUAAGCUUAUUUUAGUCACAUGUAGUAUAUAUCUCCUUAAAGCUGUCACUCUCACUUUCUUACCAUUCUCUUGAUUUCUUCAGAAACCAUCUAGUCAUCAUCUUUAUACUCUACCUGCUUCUGCAAUUAUAUAUCAUAUUAUGUUUUCAGAGCAGUUCAUUGUCAAGUUGGACUUUAAGUGACCAUUCAAGAAAAGAUGAAAUCUCACGAACCUCAAAACUUCAUUCAUGUCUUUUUACAAAUGAGAAAAAAAAAUGCAUUAAAGAUUAAUACUCAAUUUGAUUAUAUCUUGGGUUCUGUUUUUUAAUGAGUGUUCUAAGGAAAAGCUUAGAAAAGCUGCUAACUCCUCAGAAGAAAGCAUGAUAGUUUAAAGGUAUAGGGCAUAUAAAUUUAGGAUUUGAAAUAUGAUUUUUUAAUUAAGGUCAGUCCUACUCAUAAACUCAUUUUCUGCAAAGCAUUAUCAUGGCAUAAGGUUCUAUGUUCAAAAUUAUCCCAAGUAACAAAGAAAAAAAGAAUAACUGCCUGACCAGGAUUUUAACUUGUUAUUCUAGCUUAAUCAUAGAUAAUCAGCAGUGAAAACUUUCCUUUUGAAAGAAGAAAAUAUCAUUCCCUAUAAGUUAUUUGAUCUCUCUUAAACUCAAAGCUUAACAUUUCACUUAUGUUGAUAAGUUAAUGGUAAUGGAGCCAUUUGGAAUCUUGAUUGUAUAAAUGUUUACCAAAUACACUAAGGUAAGCAAGAGGCAUUUAUCUAGUGAGUAGGCAAAGAUUUAAUAUAAUAAUCCCCUAGGCAAAAGUUUAUAAGCAGUUAGAAAAAUCAGUGAAUCUUCUAUUUGACAUUUCUAGAAACCGGAGGAAAAUCUAGGGUGUCCUGGAAAAGUGAUGAGGUGUUGGGGAACCUGAUGCCAUCUGUUGCCAUUCCAUUCUAACAUAGUGCUACAGAACUGAACCAACUUAGGUUUUCAUCCCAUUGAGAUCAGCUGGGCACACUGUGAUGCUUUUGAUUUUGUCUAGAAACCUGUCACUUCAGGAUAAUUUCUGAAGACAAAGUCUGUUUCCCGUUUGGUAGGUGACCUGUUUAAUGUUUUCCCUGUGUCUGGGAACUCCUUAGUGUAAUUAGCGACCUUUGAACUCCACAACUAAUCCUGAGCUAUUUUGUAUUCCUUACUCAUCUUUAAGGCUGGACCUUUCCUUUCUUCAGAGUCCGUUGCCACAAUUAAAGAAGAAACAGCUGCAUUUCAAAGGGAUUCCGAUUCCAGAAGCUUAAUCGUGAUUGACAUGUUCUUAUUCUAAGCUAUAAGACACUCUAAGAGUCCUUUCUUGGGUUAAAACUUCAAUCAUUUUCUAAAAAAUUAUCUCACUAUGGAUUUUAUUCAUUUUCUUUGAUAACUAUUCUUUGCAUUUUUUAACUUGAAAGAUGCUUUGCGUUUGCAGUGAAUAUGAGCAACUACUUCCAGUGAAAGAUUUGGAUAGUGUCAGACCUUCUCUAGAUGCAAAAUUGCUAAAUUCCCUUUUAGUGCCAAAAUAUGAUUAUGAAAUCUGAUGUCUAUCACAUAGGUAAUUAUUCUUCAAUAAACUCGAAAGGUUAAAAAAAAAAGUGUUAAUUUUUUAGAAUGAACUCCAGAAAAGAUCGUUCAUGAUUUUGUAAACGCUUCUUUUCUCCAUUUUUUACUAAACAAUAUUUUAAAAACUUUUUAGAGCCAGCAAUAUAGUACUUAGGCAAUACCCUUACGGUGGUGGCAAUUUUUUUUUAACUUUUUAAGUAAUUGAUUCAAAUGUCAAGUUUGAAGCAGUCUUGUCAGGAAUUCUGAUGACAAUUAUUUGUUUAAAAAAUUUUUUUUAUUAAACAUUAGUCUGUCCCAUAAAAUCGUUUUCAUUUUUUUCACACCAAUUCAGUAUUUCUACUAGGUUAAAAUUAUGGUGUUUUUAUACAUUGUAUGAUUUAAGAUCUUUCAAGGCAGACAUUUAUACUUGGUAACAAUUGCCAAUUUUUUUUUCUGGUUUUUGUUGUAGUAUUUCAAAAUACUUCGUAGACAUUGAUAGACUCCUACACUACCCCUGGGAGCUAGGUAGGUGGAAUUAUCAUCCAGGCCUUCUGUAGGGACUGCUGCCACAACAGAGUGGUUGUUCCUAAGACAAAGGUCAAAAAAAGGGGUGUUAAUAAACAGUCCUCAGGUUUAAGGGACUUUUUUAGGAUUACAUCUUAAAUUCCAACAAAUCAGAUUUAGGAGUUACUGAAAGUGAAAUUGAUCCAUCCCUCAUCCAAACUUUGCAAUACUUUCCUGUUCUGACAUCAUUUAGAUAGUUAGCUGUAUUAUCAGAUUAGAAACCAUUGUACCAGGCUGCUGAAAGGAAAAGGAGGCAAAAAGCUAAACAUGGGAUGAAUUCUGAACCUUUUAACCUGGCUGAAGUACGUUGGUCCCUGUUAUGCAAAUACCUUCAAUCCUCUGCUAAGUUCAGUGGAAAUAAUUUUCUUGAAUGACAGGUUUAUUCAGCAAGGAUUCAGUUGGUGAUUAAUCCCCCUUUGAUCUAGGGUAUUUCACUUAACUACCAGUUACCUCGUUCUGACAAAGUGCAACUGAGAUUAGGGAGAUCACUAGAACACUACCAGGGUGUGCGUUUAUUCUCUAUAACCUUUUAAAGCAAGGGCCAAGAAUGCAAUUUAUUUUCAGUAUUUGAAGAUGUAAAGUCCUGUCUGCUAAGUUAGAAAGUCAAUUGAAUACCAAAUGAAGUUUAUUUCUUACGUAAUAGAACAAACAUUUCUUUUUGCUUCGCCUAACAAUGAUAUUAGGAAACAUAGGCUUUGAAGAAAGAAGAAACAAAGACUACAUUCUAAGUAUUGCUUCUAGUUUUGUUUCAUGCACUAGGGUAUACUUAACUGGCCUUGACAUAACCAAAAAUCAAAGCAGUGGCUACAACUUAGACUGAGAAAAUGCUUCUGUUUUAUUAAGCUGCAUGGUUUCUUCUCACCUUUCCCCCUACCACCACCACCACCAUUAGAAAAUGUCAUACUGUGUGGUAAAGAAAUCCAGUUGAGGAAAAUGUGUUGCAGUACACAGUUAUCCACCUUAAGACUAAUGAUUUCGAAGCUUUGUUAACUAUUUCUUUUCUUGAGGCAAAGGAGCUUCUUGUGUUUCCAUUAUAAGAAUAAUUGCAUUCAUUUUCAGAAUGCUUUUUUAAAAAAAAAAAGUGACAGCAUUACCAAAAUAGCCGAGUAAUUAAAUUUUUUCUGCCUGCCUUUUUCUCAGUUAUCUGAGUACCUCUUCUUCCAUAAUUUUAAAUUUUGAAAUAUUAUAUGGAAUUUUGCACAGUAUUUUGAGAAAGAAAAGGUAAUGUUUCAUGGUAGGUUUCUCAAUUUGCUGUUUAAAACUGUUUCAAUAGCAAUGUCAGUCUUUAUCUUGUAAGAUGUCAAAUCGGGAUUUAUUCCUCCAGUAUAUUUUAAGACCUUUAAAAAAAAAGUAUAGUGAUUUGUUACAAAAUAUGUUUUUAAAGAUUAGAUUUUGAUUAAUGAUUUAGUUAUAUACAGCAUUUUAAUGCUUAGUAAUUACUGUUCUAGUAGCAUUUUGCAAUACAAGGGAUGUAUUUAGAUUAUUAUACUUUUUUUGGCUCAGACUUUUUGUGAUCUAAUUUAUAAAUUGAAACAAUGACUCAAAGAAGUGCAUACCUAACUUACGUUUGUGCCAAGCCAGCCUCCUCUAGUUUCAAUUUAAUAACUAGUUUCAAAAUAUAUUUUGAUAGCAAGUUCCUAAACCACAGCAGAAUUGCGGAUCAGGAAAAAUACAAGAUAACGGCAUUCUAUAAAGAUAGAGGGCAGGUUCCCAUGGCUAUGUUGCUAAGAAACUAGUGUUUUUAAUCAUUACACUCCGUGCAGUCAUAUUUAAUCAAUAAAACAGGAUAUAUUUUGAAAUUCACCAUCACAGAAUAUAUAUAUAUAUACACACAACAUAUAUAUACAAGUAUAUGAAUUUACGUAAAUGUGUACAACACUAGUGUGUCUGACUUGGUGGGUUUCCCUGUGAAACAUGUCAGUAUCAUGUAAGAUGAAGAAUAUUUUAAGGGCAAAUAUUCAAAUAUCUUUCCUCCAAACACAGUAUUAGUUAAUAGUAAUGAAAUGAUUCAUUAAACUGAAAAUUGCAAAGGAACUCAUGAGUUCCUUUGUGAUUGAAACAAAGUGAUUAAAACUCUUAUGACCUGAAGGCUUUCCAACUAGCCUCCAACUGUCCGCACCAGCUGUUUCAUGGAUAUAACAUUAGUGUUUGUGUAUAGCCUGGAACAAUACAAGGCUGUAUCUGUAUCACUAGCUUCUUGCCUUAUAAGCAGGAUACUGCAAGGUCUGGUUGAUUUCUCUAAUGCCCUAGCUAAUCUGCCUAAUUGACAUCAGUGUCAUGUUAAUGUAUGAUGCACAAGCAUUUACAGAUGGACAAAUGCUCCACACUAAAAACCACCUGCUGAAUUUUUUUUCCAGUAGGAUGUGAAAUUUUGCACUUCUAAUCUGUUGAACAUUUAAAGUCAAAACUACAUGUUUCCUUUAAAUGGCCUCUUUAAAUGAUAUUUUAUGUUUAUAAAUUUUGUUAUGAAAAAUUUAAAAAUUAGUUAUUCCUCUUAAAUUUUUACUUUUUCCUUCAAAGGACUUGGGUGCCCUCUGCAGGUUAUAAAGAGAUAAUUAGUGACUAUAUCUAUUUUAAAACCCUGUGAUUUUUCUCUUUCAUACACAUAGCCUGCUUACACCCAAUUUCAAAGAAAGUGUGAGCUAAUUUAUUUAUAUUAACUCUUAUUAAUUUGCCAGUGGUUGAAGUUGGAGUUUCUUUUCUCCACUGGUUUUAUAGGUGUGUUUAGUGUGAAGAAUGUGAUACCAUUGAACUUCCAGACUACUUAGCUGGGGCUCUUUAAAUGUUGGAACUAUAGUAACACACAUUCCCUCACAGAAAGGAGAUUGGGAAAAUAGCUAUUUUGAAAGUUAUUGCAGAUGUAGGGAAUAGCUUGUUUCCCAUUAUGUUUCUAGAAUAUUACACAUUUGGAGUAAGCCUUGCUUUUUCAACAUGCAUCAUGUAAAAUUACAUGAAAGAAAAUAAUUUGAAAAUUACACAAGAUUUCUCUUUCUUGAUCUUGUUGAUGAUGAUUGUGUUCUAGCUCAAAAAACAGACCUUCUUAGAAUUUCUUAUUUUUUAAAAAAGUGAGUACUCAACAGAUAAUACUUUGGUACUGCCCGUUGCAGACAUGGGCCUACUAAACUAGAAAGAGCAUUUGAAGAGCAAAAGGCAAAGGUUCCAUCACCAUCCUGUGGAAAUACGUGAGUUGUUCAUUUCAGUACACCCAUAGUUUCUCAACAGGUGUAGCAGAUUUGUUUCUAAAGGACAUAGGAGUGCAUUUUUUAUAUGAAACCAGAACUGGAGUGGUAAUGGCACUUCUGAUUCAAUUAACUUACUUGGUGAAGCUGCCAGGGAAACUAAAUAUGAUGAGAAGAAGAGGAAUGACUGGAUCAAAUUAAUAGAAAUAGAUCUUUUUGCAAGCAACAUAAUGAUUCUGAUCAUCAACCUUGAAAAGUAAAUUAGAACAAGCAAAUUGCUGUUGAAAAAUUCUUUCAGCACUCUGCUGUUGCUACUCAGCUAGUCAUAGCUCAGCCAGAGGGAAGGAAAAAAUGCACUCGGUUUUGCAUUAACAAAGGAAACAUUAUUAAAGUGAAUGUUUACAUUGUGUUUAUUGAAGUGUUGAAAGAAUAUUUGUUGCAUCUUCAAGCAACCUGCUGCUCUCCAGACUGUUACAGUGCAUGAGUGAUAAUAAAAAUGAGUCAGUCACUUGUACAUUUUAGAAAAUAAAUAACUUUUAACAUAGUAUUUCUCAACUAUGUUACUUCAAAAUGUUUAAGUGCCAAACUUAAUGUUACCUUCUCUGCUAAAGAUUUUUGUCUCUAGGAAAUAUAUUCCAUUAAAAAAAAAAAGAAAGAAACUCAUUUAUUUAUUUAUUUGGGUAUACCUUCCAGUUACUUCCAGAUGCUUUAUGUAACUUUCCUCCCAGAAGCUGCAAUACAUAAGAAAUAAUAAGCUGAAAAUAAUCAAAAAAUGAAAACAAUUGUGAAAUUACUGAAAUGAGUAUGUAAUUGAGUAUGUAAUAUAUGCAUUGGAGAAAUACCGGUUGAUUAUUGUGAUAACUUUUGAGAGCUACAGUUAUUUUGAACUACCUCGUAAAGACUACAUUGAGAAUGAAAAAGCCAUUGAACAAUAGAUGUACCAAUUUGACCUUUAAAAGUUCAAUCUUUAUUAUAUGCAUUGAUAAAUGGGAAAGUUAGUAAUUAAAAAUUUAGAAGGAAUUUUAGCCUUUACCUUUCUAAAAUGAACAAUUUAAAUCACUCUUACACUUUAGAAAUUGAAAUAUAGUAUUUAACAGGGAUUAAAAUGUUUUACUUGGUCUCUUAGUGUUACUGAAUACAAGUUUAGUAUUCUGUAAUCCCUUAUGGAUUGGCUGAUUUUUGAAGAACUAUUUUCUUAGAUUUACCAACAGGACAAGUUGUCGGCCUUUUCCCACAUUUCAACCUAAAAAUGGUAUCUAUCACAGUUAUCAAAGAUUACCCCUUGCUAAAGGCUCUUAAGAAACUGUUAGCCUGUUACUUUAUUACUUACCAUUUCUAUAACAUGUACAUUUAUAGAGCAUCAUAUAUUUAUUUUAAGUCUAGAAUCAGUAAAAAGUUAUGUGUUUGUCAAUAAUCAAAAAAUGUUUAAUCUAAAAUAAAGUAGAUGCCACGCUUCUAAUUCUGCUUUUGCUAAGGCAAUAAUCAGUAGAAGUGGUUAGUAAUAUUUGUAGCUUGUUAACCAACUGGAGCAAAAGGACUUUUUAAUAUGAAUAACAGUGGUCUCGUGCCAUAAGUAUUUCUCUCAUACAUAUUAAAAUAGCAUGUUAUUUUAUUUAAUAUUGAAGGCCUAAACACAAUUGAACAUAAGGUAUGGCUUGGAAUUUAGAACUGCUGAGCAAUAUGGUUGAGAGGGAGACCUUAAUUUAGUCAAUAAAAAUUCAUAAUUAAUGUUAAGCUUUGUGCUCAUAUUAUAUGCCACUCUGGGAUUAGACAAAAGACAAAAAACAGUUCCAUAUUUUGAACGAUAUAUUCUACCUCCUGCAGUGUAUUAGCAUUGUAGCGUAGGAGACUAUUUCUGUAUGUUAUUAGUACAGAAACUGCCCAAAAAGGUGAUGGUUGAAGUUCCCCAGCCAGUUAAAGGGCACACCGUGGGGGCAGCAUAUCUCCAUGGGUCUAUCUCUAGCAAACAGAAUCCCAGAAACUUGAGCACCUGAUAUAGCAGAAGGAAAUAAAGAUUAUAGUAAGUAUAUUCAUGAGAGAGAAUUUUUUUUGCCUCCAGAUGUUUGGGGUUUGGAUAUGUAGGGUAAAUAUAAAUGUCUAAUGAAAGUAAUUACUAUUAUAUUUGAUUUGAUAUUUAAUUUAUUAUACUGAAAUACUAAAUUAAAUACAAAAAAACUCCUACAUACUAACUAUAUGUUUCUCCCACUGAUUCCCCUCCUGCCUCCUUCACUGAUUUUGAAUGUGUGCUCAAUUUGCUAGUAUGAGAUUUACCUCUGCCUUAUCAGUGAAGAAAAUAUGAUGUCUAUAUAGAAUUAUAAGGAAAAUAUAUAUGUGAAGAAAUGUUAGGUAAUCUAACAUUUGUAUGCUAAUGUGUCUUAGAUUUACCAACUAUCCUAAUGUGUAGUCAAUUGAUAAACUAAAUUUUUCUUUAGGAUAGUUCACAUCCAGUAGAACUUCUACCUUGGAAAACAUUCUUAGCCUUGUUUAUUUUGAAUGUAUGUGUGUGUGUGUGCAUGUGUGGAAAACAAGAAAAAUACAAGCUCUAGAGUAGUGGCCUCACAUUGAUUUAUAUUAGUGUGCCAGUCUUUCCCCUACCUCCCUAAUAUUUCAAACUUCUUGUGGACAAUGACAUUCAUUUUCAUACCUUUAUAUUUCCAGUGCCACCAGAAACACAAAAGCAGCUUAGUGUUGAUUUAAUGAAGUAGCAAAAUGUUAAAUACAUAACAAAACAGAUUGUCCUGUCACCUAAAACAAAUUAGUGAUGUUUGAGUAAUUAGGGUUUUGCAUGUGUAUAUAGAAAGGCUAUUUUGCAAACAGUGGUUCAGUCUGUAUUGGGCACAGGUGAAUUCUGCCCUGCGAUUGCCAUCUUUAGCACUUUUCAGAGAAUUUGUUGCCAUUUAUGACACUGAUCUUCAGACACACUGUGUAGUGCCUUGGCUUAAACUGUCAGACUGGCAACAGCUGAGGCUGCCCAUCAUAGGACACGUUCCUUGCAGUUAUGCUUCAGUGAACUUUAAAACAUUUGGCACUCGUAUCUUAGAAAUGUCCUUCCGAAACUCACUCUACAACAGCUUUGUGGGCUCCCUACUAUUUACUAGAGUCAAUCCUGAUUUUGUUUGGCAUAAUGAGACCUGAUAUGCUAUGACUCUCCCUAUCCUAUAAAGCCACAGCUUUCAGCGGUCCCCGUAUACUAAUGAAAUGGAGUCGCCAGUAUCCAAAAGUUCCAAGUGAUUAUUUAGAACAUUUCCAUUAACCAUAAAGGCAAAGUGGUAUAGAGAAAAUAAUACAGUCUUUGAAGUCACACAGGCCUGAUUUCAAAUCCCAGCUCUGUCAUUUACAAACUGGGUGGUCCUGGAUAAAUUACUUAACCUCUGUGGUCUUCAGUUUCCUCCCAACUUUGUAGGGUUAUUGUGAGCAUUGAAUGAUACCAAGUUAUAAGUGCAUAGGUAUUCAAUCAGUGUUCAUUCCCUUCUGUAUCAAAGACUUAUAAUGGCCUUUUCAUGGAAUUGUCUCUACCUAUAAUUAUGUGACUGUGCCUUCAGAUUAUCAAAAUUAUAUGAAUUGUCCAUGUGCCCUUGGUUUUGAAUGUUCAAUUCUGUAUUGCAGGAAUGCCUACUCAGUUGCUUGAAUGGGUGUUUGGAGUUAAUAAAAUGGCUGUACAAUUGA